AGCAGUCAGCCGGCCGGAGACAGAGACUUCACGACUCCCAGUCUCCUCCUCGCCGCGGCCGCCGCCUCCUCCUUCUCUCCUCCUCCUCUUCCUCCUCCUCCCUCGCUCCCACAGCCAUGUCUGCUUAGACCAGAGCAGCCCCACAGCCAACUAGGGCAGCUGCCGCCGCCACAACAGCAAGGACAGCCGCUGCCGCCGCCCGUGAGCGAUGACAGGAGUGUUUGACAGAAGGGUCCCCAGCAUCCGAUCCGGCGACUUCCAAGCUCCGUUCCAGACGUCCGCAGCUAUGCACCAUCCGUCUCAGGAAUCGCCAACUUUGCCCGAGUCUUCAGCUACCGAUUCUGACUACUACAGCCCUACGGGGGGAGCCCCGCACGGCUACUGCUCUCCUACCUCGGCUUCCUAUGGCAAAGCUCUCAACCCCUACCAGUAUCAGUAUCACGGCGUGAACGGCUCCGCCGGGAGCUACCCAGCCAAAGCUUAUGCCGACUAUAGCUACGCUAGCUCCUACCACCAGUACGGCGGCGCCUACAACCGCGUCCCAAGCGCCACCAACCAGCCAGAGAAAGAAGUGACCGAGCCCGAGGUGAGAAUGGUGAAUGGCAAACCAAAGAAAGUUCGUAAACCCAGGACUAUUUAUUCCAGCUUUCAGCUGGCCGCAUUACAGAGAAGGUUUCAGAAGACUCAGUACCUCGCCUUGCCGGAACGCGCCGAGCUGGCCGCCUCGCUGGGAUUGACACAAACACAGGUGAAAAUCUGGUUUCAGAACAAAAGAUCCAAGAUCAAGAAGAUCAUGAAAAACGGGGAGAUGCCCCCGGAGCACAGUCCCAGCUCCAGCGACCCAAUGGCGUGUAACUCGCCGCAGUCUCCAGCGGUGUGGGAGCCCCAGGGCUCGUCCCGCUCGCUCAGCCACCACCCUCAUGCCCACCCUCCGACCUCCAACCAGUCCCCAGCGUCCAGCUACCUGGAGAACUCUGCAUCCUGGUACACAAGUGCAGCCAGCUCAAUCAAUUCCCACCUGCCGCCGCCGGGCUCCUUACAGCACCCGCUGGCGCUGGCCUCCGGGACACUCUAUUAGAUGGGCUGCUCUCUCUUACUCUCUUUUUUGGGACUACUGUGUUUUGCUGUUCUAGAAAAUCAUAAAGAAAGGAAUUCAUAUGGGGAAGUUCGGAAAACUGAAAAAGAUUCAUGUGUAAAGCUUUUUUUUGCAUGUAAGUUAUUGCAUUUCAAAAGACCCCCCCUUUUUUUACAGAGGACUUUUUUUGCGCAACUGUGGACACUUUCAAUGGUGCCUUGAAAUCUAUGACCUCAACUUUUCAAAAGACUUUUUUCAAUGUUAUUUUAGCCAUGUAAAUAAGUGUAGAUAGAGGAAUUAAACUGUAUAUUCUGGAUAAAUAAAAUUAUUUCGACCAUGAAAA